GAUUGAGAAUUUGGGGUGGAAGACUAAUAAAGGAAAGAAACGAAGGAGAGAUCCAGGUAUUUAGUGUCAAAUUUUAUUGCCAAAUAACCUUGCUGUGGAGGAGUAUUCAUAUGAAUAAAGGUGUGGGUAUGCCCAACCUCUGAGCUUACGCAGAGGCCACCACGGGGCACUUUUUCUCAUGAUUAUACUCUUUCUGUUUUUAAGGAUUUAGAAGCAUUUCUUCUGUAGCUUGUCAAGUGCAAGGAGUCACUGUGUAAUAUUUGGCCUUUUUCAUCACCCUGUGUUUCCUGUGUCACAGGCUGAGGGGCUCUGAUAAUACAUGUGCAGAGGCUGGGCCAGUUGGGUAACCCUCCCCAAGGUCACGUGCCAGCCCAGCGAGGCACUCACUUUGUUUGGGUCCUUACAGAAAAUACCAAAUCCAGUUCCUUCUAGGGAAGAAGAAUGUCUCUCUUCCUGUUUUGAAAGGGGAGGAAGAGAGAUGAGGAGAGGUGCAGCCUGGAGGAUCACACAUCUUUCCUUCUGCAUUUUUCUACCUUCGGAAGACCCUGGCUUCCCUGCCUAGUUGAUCCGAGGGUGUUGUCGCUCUGAGACCCGUUAUUUUAGUGGAAGGUGCUGUUGGCCUUUCUACGGGGGCAUCCAGGAGCCCUUUUGCCACAGUGGCUUUUGCCAGGUUAUCUGGUAUUCAGUUAAUCACUGCCUCUCAGAUGCCACAUGGUUCCUCUCUGUGGUCACAGGUCAAGGAACCUGUAUGAAAGAAUGAAAAACAUCAAGAUCAAUGUGACGAUAUUAACAGCAAAUUUGAAAUCAAAUCUUCUUGAUUAAUUAUUCUAGUCAUAAAAAUGUUAAAAGUACAUACAACUACAUAAAUGAGCUGAUUCCUCUCUGCAAAGAUGGUCACUAAUGCUAUUUUAGUACAAUGUGAUUCCCUAUAAUACAUAUCUUUAUAAAUGCAUUUUUUUCUCCCUCACUUUUCCGGUUAAUACAUCUGGCAAACUCUUCUCUUCAUCAACUGUUGUAUAAUUAUAAAAUUAUAUAAUUAUUUAAAAAAUCAUGUUUUUUUAACUGCUCUCCUGUUGAUAGGCAAUUAGCUAUUUGUGGCUUCCUUUAUUAAUAAAUAAGGGUCAGCACACUUUUUCCACAAAGGGCCGGAUGAUACAUAUUUUAGGCUUUGCUGGCUCUAUGGUCUCUGUUGUAACUACUCAGCUCUGUGUUGCAGGAGGAAAGUGGCCGAAAAUAAUAUGUAAAUGAGUGUACGUGGCAGUGUUCCAAUAAAACUUUAUUUAUAAAGCCUCUGUUAGAAAUGGUUUUCAGAGAAAAUCCCGGUCCUUGUCUCUUCCCAAUACUGAUAGUCCCCCUUUUCGAUAAAUGCUGAGAAGUGGGAUUAUCGGGUUAAAGUAUAUAUACUCUUUGAAUUAUGCAUAAUACAGAUGUCCACUCAUUAGACCAGUGCUUAAUAUGGUCCUGGUAGCAAAAAGUUUUCAUUUAAAGAUUUAUUUAAGGUUUUUGCUUAAAAUGUAGGAGGAACCCUACCUGGGUCUCCAGAAUCUUCAGACCCUUUCUUGGGAUUAGGAAACUGGGCGUAGCCUGAGAUUUCAGCGGGGACAUCUCUGACUUCACUGUAAUUGCUAUUGGUGACAGUGUCCAGAUCCGCCUUCACCUUUUCCCAGACGACUUGGUGCUCCUGCCGCCCUGGAGGCUGGGGGAGGCUGUGGGCCCUGGCAGGCCGGGUGUUGACCUGUGCUGGGUUGGUUAUAACACAAUGCCUGGGUUCUGUUUGUAGCUACCAGAGCUACCACAUAGUUUGGGGUUGGUGUAGAUCGUCUGCUUCUCUGUGAUUCUCAAACCAGGUUCUGCCUCAGACACAGCCACAAAACAACCCUGUAAACUCCACCUUACGUGACGGUUUCACUGGAAGCAAAGGUUCUGAUAUUCUGGAAGUGGGCUUCAGUUACCCUGUAGUGCUCCUGGGUAGCCCCAAGUCCUCUGAACCCUCAGAGUUGACACCUGAGGACCAUCCCUAACGGUAUAGGCCUCGCCACCUUCUCACGCCCUGUUUUUAUAAGGCUGGGUGGUUCCUAAAAUAUUAAUAUUUCAGCCAAUCUGGUAUCCUGAAUGCUUGAAUUUCAUUACUGAGAACCCACCGAUGCCAUGCUCUGGGAUUAUUCGUGGGGCCUGCUAUAGAGCAGGCUCUGGAGAGCUGAAGCAGGCCUGACCAGGAGUGUGGCCGCCCGACCACCUCUGCCCACCAGGUAUGAGCUCCUGGUCAGGACAAGCAGCUGCCUCUGUGCGUUAGCUUGGGCUUAAACUGGCUCCUCCCCGCCUUAAAUACUCCAGCAUAUUCUUUAAAGAUCACAGGAAGUUGCCCAGGGGCCACUUGCCUAUUUCUCUGUUCUCGCUGAUGACCUCAGGACAAUUUUGUUCUGUUUCAAUUUGGCUUUUUGUUUGCCCCAGUCCCUGUCAUCCCUGGGCCACUGUUAGGAGGUGUGAGCUUAUCUGCUCGUGCCUGGGCCCCUGACUUUCCCUGCUCCUUCCAAGUGGCUUUUUAAGUAGCAGCCCCCGCUGCAACCCAGGGGAGCCUCAGCUCCUUCCUACGCUCUUGAGGCCUCUUAUAAAGUGGACAUGCAGGGAGAAGAGAAGCCUUGUGGCAGGCUCUUGCUGUCUCCUGUGUUAACAGAAGGAUUGCAGUUUUAUUAUUUUGCGGUGACUUUGAAAUGUGCUGUCACUCAAACAACCAUGUUUUUAUUGGCUUCUGCACUUGGAGGACUCCUCCAUGAAGCCCGCGGACAGGACAGAUGGCUCCGUGCAAGCUGCAGCCUGGGGUCCUGAGCUUCCCUCGCACCGCACAGUCCUGGGAGCCGCCUGCAGUGCCUCAAAGCCCUUUGAAAAAUGAAUUAAGAAGGAAAUACUUGACCCAAGUGGAUAUACUGCUACAAGGUGCAGAGUAUUUUGAGUGUGCAGGUAACAGAGCUGGAAGGGAUGUACGUGUGACUCCGCUGCCUUCACUGGCCUCACCUGCCGUGCCUGCCCCCGGAUACUGCAGUCGUAUCUCCAGAAAGAGUCCUGGUGACCCAGCGAAACCAGCUUCAUCUCCCAGAGAAUGGGAUCCUUUGCAUCCUUCCUCCACAGACAUGGCCUUAGUACCUAGAAAUGACAGCCUCUCCCUACAAGAGACCAGUAGCAGCAGCUUCUUAAGCAGCCAGCCCUUUGAAGAUGAUGACAUUUGCAAUGUGACCAUCAGUGACCUGUACGCAGGGAUGCUGCACUCCAUGAGCCGGCUGUUGAGCACAAAGCCAUCAAGCAUCAUCUCCACCAAAACGUUCAUCAUGCAAAACUGGAACUCCAGGAGGAGGCACAGAUAUAAGAGCAGGAUGAACAAAACAUAUUGCAAAGGAGCCAGACGUUCUCAGAGGAGCUCCAAGGAGAACUUCAUACCCUGCUCUGAGCCUGUGAAAGGGACAGGGGCAUUAAGAGAUUGCAAGAACGUAUUAGAUGUUUCUUGCCGUAAGACAGGUUUAAAAUUGGAAAAAGCUUUUCUUGAAGUCAACAGACCCCAAAUCCAUAAGUUAGAUCCAAGUUGGAAGGAGCGCAAAGUGACACCCUCGAAGUAUUCUUCCUUGAUUUACUUCGACUCCAGUGCAACAUAUAAUCUUGAUGAGGAAAAUAGAUUUAGGACAUUAAAAUGGUUAAUUUCUCCUGUAAAAAUAGUUUCCAGACCAACAAUACGACAGGGCCAUGGAGAGAACCGUCAGAGGGAGAUUGAAAUCCGAUUUGAUCAGCUUCAUCGGGAAUAUUGCCUGAGUCCCAGGAACCAGCCUCGCCGGAUGUGCCUCCCGGACUCCUGGGCCAUGAACAUGUACAGAGGGGGUCCUGCGAGUCCUGGUGGCCUUCAGGGCUUAGAAACCCGCAGGCUGAGUUUACCUUCCAGCAAAGCAAAAGCAAAAAGUUUAAGUGAGGCUUUUGAAAACCUAGGCAAAAGAUCUCUGGAAGCAGGUAGGUGCCUGCCCAAGAGCGAUUCAUCUUCAUCACUUCCAAAGACCAACCCCACACACAGCGCAACUCGCCCGCAGCAGACAUCUGACCUUCACGUUCAGGGAAAUAGUUCUGGAAUAUUUAGAAAGUCAGUGUCACCCAGCAAAACUCUUUCAGUCCCAGAUAAAGAAGUGCCAGGCCACGGAAGGAAUCGUUACGAUGAAAUUAAAGAAGAAUUUGACAAGCUUCAUCAAAAGUAUUGCCUCAAAUCUCCUGGGCAGAUGACAGUGCCUUUAUGUAUUGGAGUGUCUACAGAUAAAGCAAGUAUGGAAGUUCGAUAUCAAACAGAAGGCUUCUUAGGAAAAUUAAAUCCAGACCCUCACUUCCAGGGUUUCCAGAAGUUGCCAUCAUCACCCCUGGGGUGCAGAAAAAGUCUACUGGGCUCAACUGCAAUUGAGGCUCCUUCAUCUACAUGUGUUGCUCGUGCCAUCACGAGGGAUGGCACGAGGGACCAUCAGUUCCCUGCAAAAAGACCCAGGCUAUCAGAACCCCAGGGCUCCGGACGCCAGGGCAAUUCCCUGGGUGCCUCAGAUGGGGUGGACAACACCGUCAGACCGGGAGACCAGGGCAGCUCUUCACAGCCCAACUCAGAAGAGAGAGGAGAGAACACGUCUUACAGGAUGGAAGAGAAAAGUGAUUUCAUGCUAGAAAAAUUGGAAACUAAAAGUGUGUAGCUAGGUUAUUUCGGAGUGUUAUUUAUCUUCCCACUUGCUCUCUGUUUGUAUUUUUGUUUUGUUUUUGAUUCUUGAGACUGUGAGGACUUGGUUGACUUCUCUGCCCUUAAAGUAAAUAUUAGUGAAAUUGGUUCCAUCAGAGAUAACCUCGAGUUCUUGGUGUAGAAAUUAUGUGAAUAAAGUUGCUCAAUUAGAAUUUUUAGGGUUCUCUUUGAUAGGCCUGUUUUUCUGAUGUGUGUGUUUUUUUUGGGGGGGGGUUAUUUGUUUGUUUGUUUGUUUGUUUGUUUGUUUUUGAGACAGUCUCUCUCUAUCGCCCAGGCUGGAGUGCGGUGGCACAAUCUUGGCUCACUGCAACUUCCGCCUCCCGGGUUCAAGCGAUUCUUCUGCCUCAGCCUCCCGAGUAGCUGGGAUUACAGGCGCGCGCCACCACGCCUGGCUAAUUUUUGUAGUUUUAGUAGAGACGGGGUUUCACCAUAUUGACCAGGCUGGUCUCGAGCUCCUGGCCUCGUGAUCCAUCUGCCUCGGCCUCCCAAAGUGCUGGGAUUAUAGGCGUGAGCCACUGCUCCCAGCCGUGUGUUCUUUUUUAAAUUUAGAUAUGUCCAGAGAAUCCUCUCUCCUGUUUCCCAUUUCAUUCGAGAAUAUUGUUUGCUUGUGAGACGUAAGUUCGAGCCCUGCAUGCAAUGACCCUUGAAGGAAAAUAAACAGUCCUGGUGGUCCCAGACGCUCCUGCAGCCACAGCGCCUGUGACUCCUCAUGAUUCUUACUGAAGCUGUUGAUGACAGGAUAUCAUGGUGACGUUUUUGUAAUGAAAUAUUUCACAUAUUCAGAAUACAUUGGUGAAACUCAUGCUGGAGUAAAUAGUUAAUAUAUGGCCA